ACGCUAGCCAGCGUAGCUCCGGAGCCCGCGCGCCGUCGCCGCGUCGCUCAGGCCCUGACCCGCGCUGGACCCGCGCGCUAGGGCCCUGACGGCCCGCGCGGGCUCCAGGCGCGGGCAGCGGGGACGGCAUGCCCGAGAAGAGGCUCACCGCGGAGCCACCAACUAUUACAGAAGAAGAAUUUGAAGAUUCUCUGGCAACAGAUGAUUUCCUUGUAGACUACUUUAAUGAAUUCCUAAGCCUUCCAACCUUUUCAGAGGCAAUUAGAUUUAAUGCAGAUUAUGGAGUUUUUGAAGUAGCUAAUGAUGCUCCACAAUUUCUGGAAAAACAACUGAAAAAAAUUCUACAAAACCAGCAACCUCGAAAUCCCAUUUAUGAUGUUGUAAGGAAAGGAAAGAAUGAGGUUAAACCUGUUCAAAUGAAUGCCCCCGAUGAAGAUGAGACCAUUAAUGUCAACUACAAUAUUAUGUGUCUCAGUCGUGAAGAAGGUAUUAAGUGGAUCAAAAAAGAAAGACUUCCAGCAUUUCUGGAAAGUGAUUGUUACUUUGAAUACAGGUUAGCCAAAUUGGUCUCACAAGUAAGAUGGAGCAAGUCCGGCAUGAAUUUCACAGUAGGAUCAAAUUUUUCUCCCUGGAUCGUGAAAAAACCACCCAGUCUACCACCUCCUGCCACUGAAGAAGAUAAUCUUGUAAUUAUGAAAAAGUUCUAUGUAUCACUUGGUGAGGCUUCCUAUACUCAAACAAAAGAUUGGUUUGCAUUAGCAAAACAAAGUCAGCAAACAGUAUCAACCUUUUCGUUACCCUGUUGUGUACCCUACAACAAACUUAAAUCACCAGCUAUUUCAUCUGUUUCUGAGAAUUUUAUCUUUGAUGAUGGAGUUCACCCUAGGACAAAAAAGGACCCAUCUAAAACCAACAAAUUGAUUUCUGAAUUUGAAGAAGAAGAAGGAGAAGAAGAAGAGGUGUCUGUAUCUCUACAAGACACUCCUUCUCAAGCUCUUCUGAGAGUAUACCUUGAAAAGAAACAGGAUGUUGAUGAAAGCCUGACAAUGCAUUUCUCAACAUGUGAAGAAUUUUUAAGCUCCUAUAUAUACUUUAUUUUGAGAGGAGCAAUUCAGCAAAUUGUUGGAAAGCCAGUUGGAGAAACCCCAGACUAUAUAAACUUCAACAAUAUAACAAAAGUGUCAUUUGAUGAUUGUUUUGAGUCUAUUCAUGGCAAGAAUUUUUUAAGUGAAUUAGUUCAAACUACAAAGGAGAGGUCAGAAGAGAUAGAACAAACAAGUUUAAGUUCAAAGAAUGAGAGCGCUGGACCAGAGAGCAGGGCGGACUGGUGUAUUUCUCAUAGGACUUAUGACAUUGGCAAUAGAAAGGAGUUUGAAAGAUUUAAGAAAUUUAUAAAAGGUACAUUGGGAGAGAGAUAUUGGUGGCUAUGGAUGGAUAUUGAGAGGUUAAAAGUUCUUAAGGAUCCUGGAAGACAUCAAAGACAUCUUGAGAAGAUGAAAAAAUGCUAUCUAGUGAGCAAUGGAGAUUACUACCUUUCUGCAGAAAUCUUAUCAAAAUUUAAACUGUUAGAUGGAUCACAGUGGAAUGAAGAGCAUUUAAGAAAUAUUCAGUCUGAAGUUUUAAAACCUUUACUUCUGUAUUGGGCACCAAGAUUCUGUGUUACUCAUUCAGCCUCAACAAAAUAUGCUAGUGCUGAACUGAAAUUCUGGCACCUCCGUCAAGCAAAACCAAGGAAGGAUAUUGACCCUUUUCCACAAAUGGCAACCCUCUUGCCAUUAAGACCCAAAUCUUGCAUUCCACAGAUACCUGAGAUCCAGAAAGAAGAAUUCAGCUUAUCACAACCUCCUAAAUCUCCCAAUAAAUCACCUGAAGUAAAAACAGCAACUCAAAAGCCUUGGAAGCGGGAGCUUUUGUAUCCAGGUUCUUCUAAGGAUGAUGUGAUUGAGAAAGGGUCAAAGUACAUGUCAGAAAGCAGCAAAGUCAUUCAUUUAACAUCUUUUACUGACAUUUCUGAAUGUCUCAAGCCCCAGCUGGAUAGAAGAUACGCUUAUACAGAAGAACCUAGGGUUAAAACCGUGUCAGAUGUUGGUGCCUUGGGAGGAUCUGACAUGGAAAAUUUGUUGCAAUCUUUGUAUGUAGAAAAUAGAGCUGGAUUCUUCUUUACUAAAUUCUGCGAGCAUUCAGGGAACAAGUUGUGGAAGAACAGUGUGUACUUUUGGUUUGACCUGCAGGCUUAUCAUCAGCUUUUCUACCAAGAAACACUUCAGCCUUUUAAAGUAUGCAAGCAAGCGCAAUAUCUUUUUGCCACAUACGUUGCUCCUUCUGCCACUCUUGACAUUGGACUCCAACAGGAAAAGAAAAAAGAAAUUUAUAUGAAAAUACAGCCACCAUUUGAAGACCUUUUUGACACAGCAGAGGAAUAUAUCCUUCUCCUCCUUCUUGAGCCAUGGACAAAGAUGGUAAAAUCGGACCAAAUUGCUUAUAAAAAGGUGGAGCUGGUGGAAGAAACUCGACAGUUAGACUCCACAUACUUCAGAAAGCUACAGGCUUUGCAUAAAGAGACAUUUUCCAAGAAAGCUGAGGACACCACUUGUGAAAUUGGAACUGGCAUUUUAUCACUCUCUAACGUCUCUAAACGAACAGAAUAUUGGGAUAAUGUUCCUGCAGAAUACAAGCAUUUUAAGUUUAGUGAUCUGCUUAACAACAAACUGGAGUUUGAACAUUUCCGUCAGUUUCUUGAGACUCAUUCUUCAAGCAUGGAUCUUAUGUGCUGGACAGACAUUGAGCAGUUCCGGAGAAUAACUUACAGAGAUCGAAAUCAAAGGAAGGCAAAAUCUAUAUACAUUAAAAACAAAUACCUUAAUAAAAAAUAUUUCUUUGGACCCAACAGUCCAGCUUCUCUGUAUCAGCAGAACCAGGUAAUGCAUUUAAGUGGUGGCUGGGGGAAGAUUCUUCAUGAGCAGCUUGAUGCACCUGUUCUAGUUGAAAUCCAGAAGCAUGUGCAAAAUAGGCUAGAAAAUGUAUGGCUGCCAUUGUUUCUUGCAAGUGAACAGUUUGCAGCACGUCAGAAGAUAAAGGUACAGAUGAAAGACAUAGCAGAAGAGCUCUUACUACAGAAGGCUGAAAAGAAAAUCGGGGUCUGGAAGCCUGUGGAGAGUAAGUGGAUCUCUUCAUCUUGUAAAAUCAUUGCUUUUCGCAAAGCAUUAUUGAAUCCAGUUACUUCAAGACAAUUUCAACGUUUUGUGGCUCUAAAAGGAGAUUUAUUGGAAAAUGGUUUACUCUUUUGGCAAGAAGUACAAAAAUAUAAGGACUUGUGCCAUUCUCAUUGUGAUGAGUCUGUCAUCCAGAAGAAGAUUACAACUAUUAUCAACUGCUUUAUUAAUUCCAGUAUUCCACCAGCUUUACAAAUUGACAUUCCAGUAGAGCAAGCCCAGAAGAUUAUUGAACACCGGAAGGAGUUAGGACCAUAUGUAUUUAGAGAGGCACAGAUGACAAUUUUUGGGGUUCUGUUUAAAUUCUGGCCUCAGUUCUGUGAGUUUAGGAAGAAUUUAACAGAUGAAAAUAUUAUGAGUGUUUUAGAGAGAAGACAAGAAUAUAAUAAGCAGAAAAAAAAAUUGGCAGUCCUAGAAGACGAAAAAUCUGGAAAGGAUGGAAUCAAACAAUAUGCAAAUACUUCAGUGCCUGCUAUCAAAACUGCUUUACUCAGUGAUUCCUUCCUAGGCCUCCAACCAUAUGGCCGACAGCCAACCUGGUGCUACUCAAAGUAUAUAGAAGCCUUAGAACAGGAGAGAAUUCUUCUUAAGAUCCAAGAAGAACUAGAAAAAAAGUUGUUUGCAGGCUUGCAACCUCUCACAAAUUUUAAGGCUAGCUCUUCAACUAUGUCUUUGAAAAAGAAUAUGUCUGCCCACAGCAGCCAGAAGUGACAGCAUUCUUGUGAAUGUUUACAUCCUGCUGCUGAUAGGUUCAAGGAAUUCUUUAAACCAGAUUCUGCUGACAUGAGAAGCUCCAGUGAUUUGUUUUUUUGAAGGUCUGUAUCAGAGCAAGCCUAACAUCUAAAUAAAGUUUGAUUCUGGAUUUUCCAGGUGGGAAAUAAAUAAAGAAAAUUUGGCUUGUCUUACUCUCGCAGUUUUAAAAUUAUAGCUAUUCUGUACACAUGACAUACAAGACUAUAAGAACUGUUUAACUUAUUUAGAAUAAAACAACUACUAUCUAGGUUUGAAGAACCAAAA